GAGCGCGGCAGUGGCCCUGGCAGCUGGCGGAGCGGCCCAGCCCGUGUGCACGUGGCGCCGGCGCUGCCUUUCGGUUGCCAAAAUUCAGGCUGUAGACGGCGAGAUAACAAGUUUAAAACCCCGGCUAAGCCAGAAGAGCCAAAGAGGGACCUCGCCAAGGCCACUCCUCGCUCUCUAGGCCGAGAAUACUGCGCAAAUUCUGGGAGGUUUGGGCCUGGCGGCUCUCCGUUCCCGACCCCCGGCGUGGAUUCGUUCCCGCGCUUUCUGGCGUGAGGGGUCAGAGGGCGCGCCGACGCUCAGGCGAACGGAGCGGAGGCGGCAGCGGCCAUGGGCGAAGCGGGCGCCGCUGAGGAGGCCUGCCGGCACAUGGGAACUAAAGAGGAAUUUGUUAAAGUCAGAAAGAAGGAUCUGGAACGGCUGACAACUGAAGUGAUGCAAAUACGGGACUUCUUACCCAGAAUACUAAAUGGGGAGGUGCUGGAGAGCUUCCAGAAAUUAAAGAUUGUAGAAAAAAACCUGGAAAGGAAAGAGCAAGAAUUAGAGCAGCUGAAAAUGGAUUGUGAGCACUUUAAAGCCCGCCUGGAAACCGUGCAGGCCGACAACAUAAGAGAGAAGAAGGAGAAACUGGCUCUUCGACAGCAGUUGAAUGAAGCGAAGCAGCAACUCCUGCAGCAGGCAGAGUAUUGUACAGAAAUGGGAGCAGCAGCGUGUACCCUCUUGUGGGGUGUCUCCAGCAGUGAGGAAGUCGUCAAGGCCAUUUUGGGAGGAGUAAGUAUGGAUAAAGCUUUGAAGUUUUUCAGCAUCACUGGUCAAACAAUGGAGAGUUUUGUGAAGUCGUUAGACGGUGAUGUCCAGGAGCUGGAUUCGGAUGAAAGUCAGUUUGUUUUCGCUCUGGCUGGAAUUGUCACGAAUGUUGCUGCUAUAGCAUGUGGUCGUGAAUUCUUGGUUAAUUCAAGCCGGGUGCUCUUGGACACCAUAUUGCAGCUUCUGGGAGACUUGAAGCCAGGACAGUGUACCAAACUCAAAGUGCUAAUGCUGAUGUCCCUAUACAAUGUAAGCAUCAAUUUGAAAGGCUUGAAAUACAUCAGCGAGAGUCCAGGAUUCAUCCCUUUGCUGUGGUGGCUUUUGAGUGAUCCAGAUGCAGAGGUGUGCCUUCAUGUACUGAGGCUUGUCCAGUCUGUGGUUCUGGAACCUGAAGUCUUCUCCAAGUCGGCCUCUGAGUUCCGGAGCUCCCUGCCCCUGCAACGCAUCCUGGCAAUGUCCAAGAGCCGCAACCCCCGCCUGCAAACCGCAGCCCAGGAGCUCCUGGAAGAUCUCCGCACUCUGGAGCAUAAUGUGAGGAGGCCAUGAGAACCGUCAAGAAGUUCAUGGACUCAGGAGGACGUCGUGAGCAGUGCUGAGGUCAUGGAAUGUGGGCUGGGACCUUGUGUUUGGUGACAUCCUGUAAGUACUCGGCUCGCUCAAGCUAACUGCCCGGCUGGGAUCACCGCUCUAGGAGGACUCAAGAGUUCAGAUGAGUGGCCCAGGGGCCCGUCAGUGCUGUGCACCUCUCCCCCCAUGGGUGGGGGAGGAGCCUGGGGACUUGGCCAGUCCUGGAGGAGCCCUGAGACCAGGCCCUGUGGUGGGCACCACGGCACGGGGAGGUGCCUGGAGGGCUGGAGCCCACUUGGGGGGCCAUGGUCAGUCAGGGCUGCAGAAGCAGAGAAAUGCGGGAUGCCCAUGCUGGCUGGGACUCGCCCACUGCCCUGCACAUGGCGAGUGAGGGAGAGAGGCAAGGCACCUUUCCAGGGGUGCAUGGGAGGCUGCGGUCAAAGGUCCUGCACACCCGCAUGCGUGCUCACAUCUGUAGCUGCAGACACUGACCCCCAGAGACCCCCGAGCUCAUGUGGGGCUGGUGUAGGCGUGGGGUGGACGCUGGGGCAGUGUGGGCUCCUCCUCCUCCUCCAUGCGCGUGACGGGGUGGGGGUGGCCCCUCCCCUUGCCCUGGGAGCUCCGGCCCCCUCCCCACCCUCCCUGUGGCCCCAGUAGACAGAGCCCUGGCCCCUGCCUCGGGCCAGGUUUGGCAGAGGGGGCCCUGGCUGGAAACUGGAGGCAGAUGGAGGGGAGCUGGGGUUGCGGGCUGGCCGUGUCCCCUAACCCCUACACAGCCCAGCUCUGCUCCUGCUCCGCCUGGGUGUUCUGCAGGCUGGGGUGGAGGUGCUCCAGGACUGCCCCACAGCCCAGGGCCACACACCCCUGGAGCGAUCCCUAUCUCUGUCUGCGCCCUGGCCUCCUUCCUGCCAAGACCCUGACUGAGUCAGUAGGCUUGACUUUCAUAAACUGGCCAACAAGAUUGAGACCACACUUGGAGUGGAAGAUGGGGCCGUCUUAAGCCCUUGCCCCCUGCACGGGUCAGCCUGUGGCCAACGUCCUGGGCCGAGCCUCCUCCUCUUGCUCCACGCUCUUCCCACCCUGAGAGGGGCCUGGUCUGGGUGGGUCUCCUGGGACCCCCAGUGUUCGAACAUGACCUGAAAAGCAGAAAUGGAGGCUGAAGCCUUGGCAAGGAGGCCAGCACUUCCCAAUCUCACCUUCCACAGCUGAUGUGCAGGGCCGGGGGAGUGUUGGUAAUCCUCCCAGGACACACGUCUGCAUUUAAGGGUGUGCCUGACAUGAAAGGAAAUUUAUUCAAUGAUCUUUGCUAAAGACCGGAAGGGGACUACUCAGGACCAGUGCGGUGGGUGCUGGGACCAGGGCAGUGGGAUUUUGCAGUGGUGGAGAGAGAUUUAGGCUCCACUCUGAAUAUGGCUCCAGCGAGUGGGAUUUGAUAGCCCAGGAGCAGAGUGGGGUCCUCGGAUGGAACAUCACUAAGAACAAACAGCAGGGGUGGGAGGGUUCUGGCUGAAGGGAGGCGGGGUCAUCCGUCAUCACCUGGGUGCCGGAGGACGAGCAUGCUGCCCUGACGAGGAUGAUCAGAUACGGGGCGGGGCAGUUCUGGCUGAAGUCACUUAGCAGUGUUCUUGCUAAAACCGGAUUUUGCAAGGAAGUGUGCAGGUGGCCUAGAAGGCUCAAGGGCCUGAUAGAGUUUGGCCAAGCAAAGAAUCUCGUCACUGAGAAUUAGAAUCAAGGGCAGGUGGCUAAAUAGUGCCUUGUGGAUUCUCUCCGGCUUUUGCGGCCCCUCCCUCCACAUCCUGCUCUGGGUAGCCCCUAUCCUGCAGCCAUGACCCAGAUUCCUGAAGAGGGGAUGACUAUACAGGGGCCUGGAUGCUGGGUGCCGGCCUCAGGGGCGGGAGGCACCGGGAGAGGCCUGGCCGGAGAGCCGCCGGGACCCAGGUCAGGUCAGGACCCAGUGUGUAGCGGAGCUUGGGCUCAUGAGGUCAGAGCUGGAGCCACUGCACAUCGUCUCCCAGGGCCGGGGCUCCCAGAGGACAUGCAGUGUCUGCAGUUUUCUGGGGUGCCCCCGUCCUCUGCAUGGCACUCUGCGUGUUGGGGGCCUAUUGCGAGCUGCUCAUCCUGGCUUCUUGGGAGCAGUGUGGCCUAAGCAAGGGAGGCUGCCCAGGACCGGCACCUGUGGGGCGGGGCUGGUCGCAGGGUCUCGGUCCCUGAGGGCUGAUUCCUGCUGAAUGCUUCAAUGGCCAAGGGUGGAUCCCUCUCCUUCCAGCCUGAGGCUGUUUCAGGAAGAAACAGUCAGGCCUCGGCAGGUUUCCCUGCCCAAGGGGAGAGUCUGAGGAGGGGCUGACUCGGCAGGUGGAGCAGGGGGCCACUUUCAUCGAGUUUGUGUUCAGAACUCACUCCAGGGUCCUUUUCUUUUGGGGCCAGGCAGGCAGCACCAUGUGGGACAUUAUUAGCAAGGAGAGGAGGGGCCCAGGAGAGCUCACAGGGCGUUUUGGGAGCUCCGUAGAUAGGCAGGUCCUGAGGACUUUUGGAAAGGAUAGAACAAGGUCCCGGGCAGCUUUGUGGUGGUUGAGAGCGAGGGAGGAGGUGGCCUCCCUGAGCGUGGAUGGCUGGAUGCAUGCCCCAGACCCAGGGGCAGAGGCUGAGAAGGGAAGUCGGGGGCCCAGGGACCACACUUGGCAGGGUGGAGGGGGCAGGGGGAGCCACUUGCUGGGGAAACUUCACCGGAUGAUCUGGGCUGAGGACGCGCGAGUGUGGAAGAAAUGGUACCUCCCCCAUGCCAGAUGCUGCCCACCACCGGCACAGGGUCAGAGUUGGGGUCAGCGGGGCAGCCGUGUGCCCCCAGUGGGAGCUUGGAGGUCACGGAGGAAAUGCGAGACCAGAUGCAGGCAGGGGAGUCCUCCGGAGCCUGCAGGAGGGGGCCGCUGGCUCAGGGGCACCGGGAGACCCCCACAUGGACAGGGUGGAAAGGGCUUUCUUCAAAGCCAGGAUCUUGUCUCCAUCACAGCGUCCCAGCAACGCAUUGGGAGUGCUUGCUGCCAGGAGGCUCCCCGGUCCCGCAGCAGCCCCUCAGCGGCUGCCCUCCAAGGAAGGGGCGCACAGACACUCCAAGGCUCCACAGCGCGUGGGCCAGGGGCCGGAUCUACCCCUGGGGCAGUGGGACUGAGCGUGAGCCCAGCGCAGCCCCUCUGACUGCGUCAUUGUUAGGGGCCUUCUCGGAGCUAGCAGACCUAGAACCAGGCCUAGGGGGUGGGGGCGUGCCUGGAUGUGCACUGGGGGGGUGUCUGAACCCUUAGUUAGGACUGCGGGCCCUCCUUUCCACUUCCUUCAGUUCCUGGGGUCUGGGGCAUCCUAGCCAUGCGUGGGGCCUCCCUGCUGGGAUUGGAGACCCCCUGACAGCUGGGGCUGGUCCCAGCAUCUUCGCUCUUCCCCCAGGAGGACUUGGACGCAGGGUCUUCUCUGCUCCCCGUCACACAGAGGGUGGCACACCCGAUGGGAACUCUCAUUUAUCACCAAACCAAAAGAUGGAGAAACUGACAGAGAAGGGCUGCAAGCAGCUACGGCAGGGCGGUGUGUGGAAGCAGAUGGGAUGGGCAGAUGGAGGCGGGGGCCAGCAUCGCUGCCUUCUUGCCCCUCCCAGAGGACCCCAGGUCCCCAGCUCGGGCGCCCCACCCAGACUGGUAACGCCUGCGUCUGCUGUUUGGCACCGGGAGAUGAAUCACUUGCUUUUCAAAUUAGAAUCUUCCUUGCUGUCAGAAAUGUUUCUUCUCUACAAGGAAAUGGAGGUGAAAUUUUUAUAUGGGAAGGGUAGCUCCCUUGGCGAAUUGCAGGGCAGCGGAGGGCGGGUUCGGGGAGCCGAGUGCAGCCCGAGGUGCAGCUUUCAGGCUGGGAGGAAGCAGCUGCUUCCGGCUCCUCGGGACACGAGACGGGGACAGCGUGUGCUCGGCGGGUGGGAGUGACGCUGCCCACCUGCGGGCGUCUCCUGGGGAACGGGGUAUGUGGGCUGUGUGGCGGUACGGAGCCCAGCGCUGAUAGGAGGCUGCGCUGUCAGGCUGCAUUUGACCAUUUAUGGAACCAGGCCAUGAGGAGGCCCUGAAUUAGAAAGGCAUCCAGACCCAGGCUGCAGCCUCAGGCCGGGCACUGUCCCCUGCAUGGCUCCGGCGUCCCAGCUUGGUGUUAUCAGAACACAGAGGUUGAGGCUAUGGCUCCAUCUGGGCUGUUAGCACAGAGAAAAAAUGCCCAAAUGACUUGGUAAAGGGCGGGCUUCCUGGCCCCAUGGCUGCACGGGUGGGCUGGCUUCCUGUGUUUGCUGAGAUUUCUUUGAGGCAGCCCCACGGUAGAGUCCACUCUGGGUCCCGGCCCUGCGCUGGGCGCUGUGCUGAGCGCCUCUGUGGCUGCCAUCAUCUGAUUUUCAGCGCACUCACAGGCAGGCGCCAGGCUUCACUUUAAAGAUGGGGAAGCUGAGUCUCAGGGAAGUGGGGUCUGUGCCAGGGUCUUAGCAGGACUUCUGGGGUUGCUAGGACCCCCACGGGGCUGGGCUGGGGGUCUUCAUGCCAGGCCCAAUCCCUUUCCCAUAGUUCCCCCCGCCGGCACUACCCAACAUGUGGUCUCCGGUCAUCUCGUGCUGUCUCCACCCCUCCCUCCGCUUCUCUGCUGGAGUUGUCCCUGUCACCUUACCCCAGAGCCUUCUUUGUUCUUACAGUCCCAGGCGGAGGGUACCUCGGAGCACACUCUGCAGCCUCCGGCUCUCCCUCCUAAGUCCACCUGCCCGGCCGAUUGGGCUGUGUGGUCACUGUCCUCAAGACCUUAUGUGCCAUGAGGGCUCAGAGCCCUGAGCCUCAGCACAGGAAGUGCCACCCAGGCAGCCAACACCUGCUCAGCGGGCGGAUGGCCUUGCCGACUCGGCUUUGCUCCCGGGAGCCUCCUGGAGAAGAAGCCACAGGGAGACGGACAGCCCUGGGCGGCUCCAGCUUGCCAGCUCCACAUCCAAGGUCCUCCUUCUGGGGUGGGGUUACAAUCUGUUCAAAGCAUAUGCCCAGAAUAACAUUUUUGAAAGUCUUUAAAAAUGGGGUAAAGCUGACGUACCACGAAAGACACAAAUCUUAUCUCGUGCUCAGGUCUUUGCGUGUCUGCGCCCGUGUAACCGCCGUGCGUGUCAGUGAGUCCCUCCAAGAGCACGCCAGAACCACAGAGAACCCCUGGUCCCCCCCAGGGACUCCCCCGAGUCAUGACCCCCAGAGGUGACCUCUCCUGUGAUCUCUGACUUCCCAGCCUGUGGGGGUCUUGGGGACUGUGUUCUCCCUGCUGUUAGAGUACACAGGCCCUUUCUUUUCAUGGCUGUGCAGGGAGGGAGCGGGAGACACCACGGGUUGUUCCUUCUGCCGAGGGACACUGGUGACUUCAGGUUGUCUUUCUAUGGCUUUCGUGCUGGCUCUGGUGGGACCUGCGCUCAGCAGCAGACACUGGCCCUGGGGGUUGUGUGAAGCUUUGCUGCUAUUCCCCACAGGGUGGGGGGGGGCCAGUUACCCUCCCCCAUAGCUGUGGGGACUCCCGGGACCCUUGUCGUCAGCCUUUGCCAUCUCAGCUCACCUGGCGGGGGUAGAAUAACGUUUUGCAGGAAAGUUACAGACUUCCUGUCAGCUCAACUCUGCAGAAGAGGAGUUUGGUGGGAAGUUUUUCCAGAGUCUUCCCUCGGCCUGGGGCACAAUGUCACUGAAAUGCUGGAGCAAUCAGGGGCCAGCCCUCAAAUGGAGUCCUCGCCUCCCCACCGAAAGGCCAGGCCCGUUCAGAGAAGACCCCGUGGACAUGUGGGGCGUGCAGGCUAGGCGGGGUGGGGCUGAGUGGCCAGGUGUCAGGCAGGGCCUUUGGGAACAGAAGGUGGGUCCCUAGGGAAGUGGCGGUCACCGUCAGCCUGGCGAGCAGUGGCCCUUGUGGAAAGGGGGCUUCGGACGUGCUCGGGAGAUGCAGAACCCCGUCUGUGGGAGAGCUCCUGAGAGUUAGGGGCCAGGCUCAGCUCCCAAGGCUGCCCUGACAGAGGCCACACGCUGGGGAGCUAAGAUGCUGAGCCUCUCACAGCUCUAGAGACUGGAAUUGGGGAUCAGGGCAUCCUCAGGCCCCUGCCCACUCUGGAGGCCCGAGGAGAGGGUCCUCCCUGCCUCUUCCAGCUCCUGGUGACCCCGGGCGUCCCUCUGCGUGCAGCUGUGUGGCUCCAGUCUCUGCCUCCAUUGAAACGUGGCUGUCCUCCCUGCAUCUGUGGGGCUGACUUCCCUCUUCUUACAAGGAUGCCGUCAUUGGAUGAGGGCCCACCAUACUCCAGUGUGAGCUCACCCUAACUUGAUUACAUCAGCAAAGACCCUAUUUCCAAAUAAGGUCACAUUCUGAGGUUCUGAGUUGACAUGAGUUUUUAGGGGGGCCUGCUCAGCCCAGGACAGUAUGUGGUUUAAGAAAGGGAUUUCCCCAGAAUGAUCUGCCUGCCGUCUGCAUCCAGCCGCAGACCCUGGUUCCUGCCGUCUGGUCAGGGCUGGCCCUGGGUGAGCUGGAACCCUCUGUCCCUGCACCCCCAGCACUCCCACCCAAAAUGAACUUUGGGGACAGACAUCACAGCUUAGGGCACCCGUGGGGUCUUCAGAGGCUGAGCUGGUACCCAGCUCGUUUCCUCCCUCACAGAUGCAGCCAGGCAGUGAGCAGCCGACGGGUGCCUCAGUGUCCCAUGCAGCACAGCCACGCAGAGCAGGCGAGGGCCAGCCCCCAGGAAGCCGCUUGUGCCUGCCCGCAGUGGGACAAACCUCGGCACUGAGUGUGUCCACAGAUGCCAACGCCCCUCAGACGGAGUGAGUUGAUGACUGUUAAAUGCAACAAUAUAAAUGGCCUUGUAUUUUGUAUAUCUUUCCUUUUUUGUUUUAUUUUUCUAGCUGAUCUUUUUUACUCUAUUUUGCAAAAGUUAGCAGUCUGCAGGGUGCUUCCCCCUGGCUGGCUGGAGAAGCCCCAUGUGCCGAGCCUGGUCCGAGGUCCUCUGAGCCCCCACGUCGCCUCGCUAAGUUGCUGUGCCCUGACCCCAGUGUGGGAGGGGCCAUCAGAGCACAUGUGCCUUCUACUUGGUGAGGGCGGCAUUAUCUUGGGGAUGCAACUGCAAUAAUCAAGAAACUUAGAAAUAUUUCGGAUGAAUUAACUGAGAACGCAGUGCACUCACUGGCAUGGCCACCUGCCCUCACCUGGGGCGUGCCUCCGGCCCUGGCACUGCUCUGCCCCACCCAGUUGGUGGAAUCAUGGAAGCAGAAGAGGGGUGGUCCCUGACUCGUGUUUGUGCUGUGGAGACGCCCGCAAAGGCCAGGACACUUGCAUAGAAUGCUCCCGGCACUCUCCCGUCUCCAGGGCUGUGUGUAAGAGUCAGUGACAGAACUGUACGCAGCGUGCAAGAGACAACUGCCAUCACUGCCACCUUGAAGGGCAGCCUGGGCACAUACUGUCGAGGGACAAGGAACUUGCUGACAGCAGAAGGCUUCAUGCCACAUGCUUCGGUCUGUAUACAGUCCAAAUCCGGCAAAGUGGCACGCAACACUGUCCAGGGGUUCACUGCACAUGGCAAAGCUGUCCUAGAGGGUAAGGAUGACAAAUGCCUGUGCAGGAGGGAGGUCGCCUCUGGGAACCCUGGGGGAAGCAGGAGGGAUGUGUUCCAGCUUUCCUGGGUGCCUGUCUGGCCUCUCUCUGCCCAGAGCCCGCCCCCACAGCAGCAGACACUGGACGGGGUCCCAGGCCAAGGAGCACUCCACUCAGUAGGGUGUGGGGGCUUCCCUCCUUUCAGGAGCUCAUAGAGUGAGGGGGCCCAGGGAUCAGCAUGCAGCUUUCACCCCCAGCCCCAUCUGGGACCAGCGUGCACUUUCAUCCCCAGCCGCCGUCUCUGCUUCUGGCCCUGCCGGGACUUGGGGCUGCCUGCGCAUUAAAUGGCCCAGGUCUGUGUCCUGGUUACUCAAGCCUGAGAGAGCUGCCACCCUUGUAGGUCAUGGCUGCAGGAAAUCAGGCUGUCCCCCAGGUCUAGGUGGGUCUGCCAAAAUGCCCCGAGACGUGAGCAGGGCCGUGAGGUCAGCCCUGGGUGGCGCCGCUCCUCCUGCUCGUGUGCCCAGAUCAAUCGGCUGCCCCCGCUGGAAGGGGACGCUGUCCCUGCUGGGGUCCGGAGCCCACUUCGGGCUCCCUCUCUAACCAACAGUGGCUCCCUGGAGACUCUACAUGCCCCACCCUUGCCCUCUGCUCCACUGCUGGGACCACCUUUGCUCUCAAGGACUGUGGACACCGGUGAAGAGGGGCACCCGGUCGAUGCCAGCUGGACUCCGUCCACCCCUCGAGAGCCAGGGCGUUGGGCUCACUGUCUUCCCCAGAGGAAGCCUCGCUGGGGCCACGGGAGGCUCGGGCCUCUGUUCCUCCGGCACAUUCUGGCACGGUGGCAGGGGAGGCUCCUUAGGAGGAUGAGGGGACGGAGAAGGCCCCAGGGGUCUCCUGCAGGCAGCAGUGUUUGCUCUGCAGGGCCUGGAGGUUCAGGCAGGGAGGUGGAGGCGACUACAUGUGGACGCAGGUUAAAGGACAAGGAUUCUGAACAUGCCGGGGCUGGGUCCCGGCACCAUCAGAGCCAAGUCACCGGCUCCCUCGGGGAGGAGAGAGCUGUGAGGGCUGAGUCACCGGUGGGCUGGAGUGGAGGGGAGGAUAGGGCGACAGGUGAGGACACUUCAGGCCGGGCAGGCUUCCAGCGUGCGGAAGGGGCCGGUGGGUCAGAUGGGGGGUAGGGUGGAGGCACUGGCUGCGUGGCUUCAGCAGGCAUCACCCUGGAAUGUGCUGGAAUAACAAGCAGAGGCGGCGUGGAGCAGGAUGGAGGGCAGAAGUGCAGAGAUAGGAGUGUGUGAUCCUGGGUGGAGGCGCUGACGCCUGGCCGGCGGAGACGACACUUCUGGAGCCUCGCUGAGGCUGGAUCCCAGGCUCAAGGGGCGGGCCCACCACGGGGGACCCCAGGUCACAACAAGGGGCAGCUCAGAGCAGGGUGGGGGCCCCCAGGCCACCCAGGAGUGGAAGUGGCUCGUGAUGCUGUGGGUGCUGCGCUGUGAGGGGCUCCUGGUCCUGCCGGCCUCCCAGCUACACGUGGCCCACUCGCCUCCACAGCCGCCAAGCCUCCCUUGGGGCUCCUGCUCUCGGGGCUGGGCUGGAGGGGCCUGGGAGUCCCAGCGGGCGAGAAAGCCGGGCCCAGGGGAGAGCAGCAUGCUGGGUCAGGAGACCGGUCGGGGGCUCGGCCGGGCCUGGAGUCCAGCGGGCAGGGGCUGGCAGGGAGUGGGCAGGGUGCCCGCCACCCCGAGGGCCACCAGGGAAGACCAUCUGGAUUGGGUUUGCGGUGGAGGCUCGCCAGCAGUGUUUUGACUCCAGGCAGGUUUCAGAGUGUGAACGGCCCCCGUGUCAUCUGCUGGGUCCCUCUGCCAGAGGGUUUCUGAAAGACAGAUGGCCACACGCGGAAGCUGUCGGCGGCGUGUGGGCCCAGCGAUGACGGGGGUGCGAAUCCUGCUCUUCCUCCCUCGGCAGCCAGCGGUCUCUCAGUCCUCUCCCGUGUUCUCACUGUACCCUAGAAAGCAAAGCCCGAGCUCCUCAGCAUGCUGUGGGGGCGAGUGGGCAGAGCCAGGCGUCCUGCGGGCACACAUGGCUGUCCCUGUGCCUCCAUGAGCGGGGAGGGGCGCUGGCGGGAGCCCCCACACAGGCAGCCUCCCCACCUGGGACCCCACACAGGCGGCCUCCCCACCUGGGACCCCACCCAGGCCUCCUGACCUCAUGGGGCUGGGCUUGGCUACAGGAGGGCGCUUUGCGUGGAACCUGAACCUGGCCUGGCUUUGCCUCCGUGGUUUUCGGCACAGGGGGAGGGGCCGGCUGAAUUCCUCCGCAGGAUCCAAGGGGCUGUGCAGACACGGGCCGUGACUGCUGGGUCCUCCGUGGAGAAAAUCAAUACCAAGUUGGAGUGAGUCCCCAGGGUUCAUGUAUCACUCUGCACCCGGAAGGAACUUUCUGGAAAUGCAAUACAUCCCUGCAAAGUGGGACUCAGGGCUCUUUCCUGUCACUGUGCAGAAGGCAAGGUCUCAAAGGGAGAAGAUCGGAAGGCUGGGAGCCCGGGAGCCCGCCUGGGAGCCUGCCUGGGCCUGGGUCUCCCCUCAGGGCUGAGGAGCCCCGGGCCCAGCGCCCACGGUCGCUGUAGCCAAGCUCACAGGCCCCACCUCCUGCCUGGCCAUGCUUUUGCCCACGUGGGCUGCAGCCAGGGCCUGGUCGCCACCCUCCCCAAUGUGGCCCUGAGGCCAGUCCUGUGCUGGCCUGUAUUGACACGCCGGCUCACUCAAAUCGAUUCUUGUCAAAGCCGUCGUGGAAAGAACAGCUUUCAAAAUAGAGCCCAAGAAGACGUGGGCUUCCACUGUGAGAGCCUGGGUGCUGGCGGGCUGCCCAGGGUGCCUCCUCUCUCUCCAGCCGGGCGUGGAGCUCCACGAGCAGCUCCUGGCUGUUGCAGGGCUGUGAGAUGUUCUCGUUUGUUCAGCCGGAAGGUCUAGAGAAAGGGGCUGAGGGGGACGUCUGAGCACCCAGCCUUGAGGAGGAGGCCAGGACUGAGGCCUGGGUUCAUUCCUAAUGUGUCCCGAGGACAAGCACAUGGAACGGGCUGUGUUCUGGCUGCAGACCGGCCUGGGAGCGCCCUCGCUGGCCUGGGAACGGGCAGGCUGCGGGGCAGAGGGCAAUGGACCUUCUGCCUAGGUGCGAGGGGCUGGUGUGCAGCUCCGCGCCCCGGGGACCCCAUCCCAGCCCCUCAGCCAGCCCCUCUGCAGUGGCAGUUUUCUCUUCCUGCCAAGACCUUGGACGGAGUCUGCACCCAUCCCUGCACGUGGCAGAGACAAAACCCACAAUCAGAUACACAGGAAGGGCCGGGGUCCUGCCACCUGCACGUUAGACCCUGAGGGUGACGUUUGCUCUUUGAUCCUCUGGUCCUUUGCGCUCCGGGGGCCUCUGCCUGGCAUGGAAAUGUUGAUUCUUCCCUGUCUGCCUAAGACAGUGUGAUUUUCAGACUAGCAGAGGAGGAAAUGUCCGGCGGCUGUCCUGUGGGGGUCCACCCACCCUCGAGACUGUCAUGGGCCGCGUGUCUCCCCCGGAGGCUGUCCUAUCCUAUCGGGCUCUACCCACCCUCAAUACUGUUAUGAGCCACGUGUCUCCCCCCUGGGCGGCUGUCCUAUCCUAUGGGGGUCCACCCACCCUCGAUACUGUUAGGGGCCACGUGUCUCCCCACUGGGCGGCUGUCCUAUCCUAUGAGGGCCCACCCACCCUUGAUACUGUUAGGGGCCGUGUGUCUCCCCCAGAUCUGUAUGCUGCAGCCCUAAGCCCCAAUGCCUCCGCAAGGGACCUUACUUGGAGAUGGGGUCCUCACAGAGGUGGUUAAGGUAACAUGAGGCUGGUGGGGUGGCCCUGGCCCAAUCUGCCUGGUGUCCUUAUACGGAGAGGAGAUGAGGACACAGACCCACACAGAGGGAUGGCCUUGUGAGGACAGUAGCAGGAGACAGAGCCAAGGAGAGAGGCCUCAGGAGCCAGCGGAGCCGCACCCUGACCCUGGAUUCCACCUCCUGAAUGGUGAGAGAGCCAUUCAGGCUCUCUCUGUUGAAGCCCCCAGGCUGUGGGACUUGUUACAGUGACCCGGGAACUCACACGAUAGUCACAGCACAUUACAGCUGACAAAGUGAGCUCCUUCCGUGGAGACGCUCCUCCCAGCAUUCCGGUGAGGUGGGGGCUGGCACGUCACCCCCACUCUGGAUGAAGAGGCCGCAUCAGGCGGGAUGGGCUUGGCUACGCUGCAGUCACAAACAGCCCCACAGCUCACCAUGGGCUACAGCACAAGUUCAUUGCCUGCACUUCGGGGUGGGCACCCACUUGCCCCUGUUCCAGCCGCUGUGCUUGGCGUGGCUCCCUCCUCACCAGGACCUGUGACUGUGACGCAUCAGAGGAGGAGGUGCUAGGUGGAGACAACGUGGAGACUGAGGGUGAGACUGGAGGAGGGGAAGCCCCCGUUUCUUAUUGAGAGCCCUACGGGGUCAGGCCAAGGAGCGCAGGUGGCUGUGCGGGAAGGAGCUGCACUCUGCUAGGUGUGGGGGCUUCCCACCUGCGCUCCCAGGUGAGCCGUGGCCAUGCCACCAGGCCCCUCAACCCUGUGCCUGCCAUGCGGCCCUCUCGAAGGACCUCUGGAUAUGUCUGGGGAGUCCUGCUCAGCCUGGCCCCAGUGGAGUCUCUGCAGCAAAUAAGCACACAGCAGCAGCAGUCACUGCACCUGUGGCCCUGAGAGGCUGUGAGCACACAACAUCCUGGCUGGAAAGAGGGGAGGCCUGGGGUCCGGGCAGCUUGCGGGGCCAGCUGUGCACCCAGUGACAUCCUCAUCACCACCCACGCCGAGCACAGCAGAGACCCCGAGCCGAGGGCAGAAGGAGCACACGGUCACAGGAAACCUUUCCUUCCAGUUCUCUGUGCCUGCACCCAGCACUUCGUGUCUAGGGAUGAAUUUAAUCUGCACGGUGACCUCUGAGGUGGGCACUGCCACUGUCCCAGCUCUAUAGACACGGAGUGUGGCGGGCAACAUAGGAAACAGCAAGCCUUUGAGCGGAGGGGGGUCUGGCUGUGGCUUCCCCUCUUUGUUGAAUGGUGUCCCCACAGAAAGAUCUGUCUGUGUCCCAGAACCUGUAAAGAUGACCUUAUUUGAAAAAAGGGUCUUUGCAGAUAUAAUCAGGUCAAGACCUGGCAGCGUGAUCGUCCUGGGCUGUCAGGCUGGACCACAGCGCCUGGUGUGAAGGACAAGCGCCUUCAUGAAGAGAAGAGAAAACCCAGGGAGAGCCACAUGGAGAGGGGCCGAGGCCGUGGGAGGGCCAGGCAGGGACUGGAGGGAGGCAGCCACAAGCCAAGGAACGCCUGGGCCACCAGAAGCUGCCAGAGACAAGGAAGAUCCCCCUCUAGCGCCUCUGGAGGGAGUGCAGCCCUGCCCACAGCUUAAUUUGGGGCUUCUGGUCCCCAGAGCUGUAAGGGAAUCAGUAUCUGUUGUUGAGGCCACCUGGCUUGUUGCAAGAGCCCCAGGACACGCGCCCACUUGGCCACGUUGCCCAGGCGGUUGUGGUCGAGUGCCCAGGGUUCCGGCCCCAGCGCCUGCACUCCUGACCACACAGGAGGUUGACGCCUGCCGGGAAGUCUGCUCACGGCACCCUCUCUCUUUCCGGAUUCCAGUGCUUCCUGCGGUGCUCUGUGCAAAGGAGUGCUGCCGGCUCCCAUCCCCAGCCUCUCAGGGCUGGGAGGUGACAUCCAGCAGCAAGCAGGGGCCCCGCUGUCUGCGACAGCGUGGCUGAGAGUUGGUGCCGGCCAGGUGUGUUGGCUCAUGCCUGUAAUCCCAGCGCUUUGGGAGGCUAAGGUGGGAGGAUGGCUUGAACCCAGGAGUUCAAGGCUACAAUGAGCUAUGCUUGCACCACUGCACUCCAGCCUGGGCGAAUGUGAGACCGUUUCUAUAAAAUACAAUAGAGAGACGGCGAGUCGGUGCCACACGAUUGGCCCUUGGUGUGUUUUCCCUGCCCAUCAGAGCUACCCCAAGGAACUGAGUGAGCAAAUGUGUGCCUGUCUGCUCACCUGCUUAAGAUGCAAAGUGUCGAAAGCAGGGCCCCACCCAGCAUCUUCCCCUCCCGCAGGUGCCUGGCACGCUGGGCUCCUGCCGCCACAAACCGACGUGACUUGGUGAACGUAAGUGAGCACUGGCUGACCGGAUCAUGUUUAAAGGAAUCCUUUAGGGGAACCACUCUGCAAAGAAAGUAACCCUCAGUAACUCGCUUUUAGUUAUAUGUGGACUUCACCUUAUCCGGCUUCCAUAAGGUGGAUUUGCAGAAAGCCGGGGCGGUGGCGCGGCGGGAGGCGUGGGAGCUGGUGGGAUUCUCCGCAGGUGCUGCUGGGCCGGGCAGUGGCUCCGGUGGGGGGCGCUGUGUCUCCAGGCCCUGACCUGGCUCCCGCUGGGCCGGCUGUGGCAGGGAAGAGCCAUUUUUCAUGGCAGGGGGGUGGCUUCACACCGGCCCAAGUGCCAGUAUGUUCCACAGUUCUUUUUGCUGACGGAAUCAGCCAUCAGCUCAGCCCAGGUGACUUCCAACCUAAUCUAAACAAGGUGGGGUCGGUGGACUCAGCUCUCACAAAGAAAGACACGGUGACGUCGGGCGUGGCCACGUGAGGCAGGGGUGGGGAGAGGCUGACAGCCUCUGCCUCUCCCUCCACCGGCACCGCCCGCCCCAAGCUCACGUGGCCCUUGCGGACGUCAUUCCUUCACUGGGUCGUGCCAAGCAGCAGGGGUGCGGCUGUCCCAGUCCUCACGCCCUGCCCUCCUCGGGCAGCCUGGGUGUCCGCUCCUGCACUCAGAGCACUCCCCGCCAGGCACCCCCCGCCAGGCACCCCCCAUCCACACCCAAAGGCAGGCCCAGGCACAUGGCUUGGGUGACAGAGUCUGUUUGGGGCGAUGCCUGCAAGCCCUGUGGGAAAUCGGGGUGGAGGGAGCGGGCGGGGCCGAGCGGCCGCGGGAACGAGCAGUGCCCUGCCUCCAAGGGAGCCCCGGGUCCUCUCCCCACUGGCUGGCCCUGUCGUGGACAUGAGCUCUCAGGUUUCUGACGGGCUGAGCGUAGUGGCUGAGGGCUCCCUCAGGCAGGGGCAGGUGGGCUUGGGCCAAAGAGAAACCUCUUCCCCGAUAGGGGACACAGCAGACAGCCACCAGGAGCCGGAGUGGAGGGGCCAGGCUGUGCUCAGCCUCACGACACACUGGCGUUCGCUCAAGCUCAUGGCUGGCGUUUAGGAGGGCACCGCGAGCACCUACUGAGCUGGGAUGAGGUCGGAGGCUGCCCCUGCCCAGUGAGAUGAAUGCCCCGGGGCCAUGUGGGCUCUUGGCCGGGUGGUGCCAGGAUGUGCCUGGAUUUCAGAGUAGGUGGUCAGGGGUGGCCACCUGCUGGGAGUCUGGACCGUGGAGCCGGGGCGACUGGGCUUCAGCUUCAGUGGCUGCACAACAUCCAAAAGCAGGGGGCCCUUGAGGACCCAGCCCUGCUCUCCGGGCAGUGGGCACUUGGCCCCAGCGCCCCCCCUUUCUCGGUGCGAGGCCGAGCAUCUCCCAAGUCUGGUGCCCACCCGGCUGCCUUGGCCUCUGCCCACUCCAAGCCAGCUCUUACUCCGCCACAGGCCCGGCCCCUCUCACUUCCAGCCUGGGCCCCACUGUCACUUCCCAUCAUCUCCCUCCUGGGUGACAGCCUUGGGAAGGGUCUCUGGCCUAGACUCUGAUCCCAGGACACGGCCCUUCCUGCUCCUUGGUGGCCUUCCUGGGCCUCCAAGUCCGCGACCAUACCCAUGACCUGCUGCCCGCUGCUGGUGGGCCUCAGAUUUCCCGGAAAGAGGGAAGAGGCUCAGACCAGCCCAUAGCAGCUUUCCAGGUGAGGCCGUGAUCAUGAGCAGUCCAGGGUCCGCUGCCUGGUGGGGGCGGGACCGCAGGCUGGGCAGGGACAGCAGGCAGGGGUCCCUCCCCCCACACAGCCCCCCCUCCUGUGCGGGGCUCUGGGGUCCUGCCUUACAGGGGUCCUGUGUCACCUCAGUGGGGAGCAGGAGAUGGGCCCGGGGCUCGGGGCUGCCAUCUCCACUGCAUGGUCUGGGGCUGAGCUGUCGUGGAGCAACUCGGGCCACAUGUUUGUAAUUUGGGGACAAUUCUGUCUUCCUGUAAUUUUAUUGUAUUUAGUAAAUGCGGUUUAAUUUUCUUCCUGUA